GAGAUACCCUGAAACCUCCCCCCUCUGACCCCGCAGCCAGGCCCCAGGCUGGCCGGGAGUGGCCCCUCACACUGGUUCUCCCCACUUUCUCUGCCUGUGGCAUCGAAGGCCCCGGGCACCAUGGCCCAGGCCCUGGGGGAGGACCUGGUGCAGCCUCCCGAGCUGCAGGAUGACUCCAGCUCCUUGGGGUCCGACUCAGAGCUCAGCGGGCCUGGCCCAUAUCGCCAGGCCGACCGCUAUGGAUUCAUUGGGGGCAGCUCAGCAGAGCCAGGGCCGGGCCACCCACCUGCAGACCUCAUCCGCCAACGGGAGAUGAAGUGGGUGGAGAUGACCUCGCACUGGGAGAAAACCAUGUCCCGGCGGUACAAGAAGGUAAAGAUGCAGUGCCGGAAAGGCAUCCCGUCUGCCCUGCGCGCCCGAUGCUGGCCCCUGUUGUGUGGGGCCCAUGUGUGCCAGAAGAACAGCCCUGGCACCUAUCAGGAGCUGGCAGAGGCCCCUGGAGACCCACAGUGGAUGGAGACCAUUGGCAGGGACCUGCACCGUCAAUUCCCUCUGCACGAGAUGUUUGUGUCGCCUCAGGGCCACGGCAGGGGCUCCUGCAGGUGCUCAAGGCCUACACCCUGUAUCGACCGGAGCAGGGCUACUGCCAGGCCCAGGGGCCCGUGGCUGCUGUGCUGCUCAUGCACCUGCCCCCAGAGGAGGCCUUCUGGUGCCUGGUGCAGAUCUGUGAGGUCUACCUCCCUGGGUACUACGGGCCCCACAUGGAGGCUGUGCGGCUGGACGCCGAGGUGUUCAUGGCCCUGCUGCGGCGGCUGCUUCCGCACGUGCACAAGCACCUGCAGCAGGUGGGCGUCGGACCCCUGCUGUACCUGCCCGAGUGGUUCCUGUGCCUCUUCGCCCGCUCCCUGCCCUUCCCCACAGUGCUGCGUGUCUGGGAUGCCUUCCUCAGUGAGGGAGGAGGACUCACAGGGGUGGCUGUGGAGGCCUGGGGCCAGAGAGGCCACUGUCCCCAGGGGCCAGGCUACAGUCUACGAAGCAGGGAGGGCUUGGAGCCAUGAAGCCAGAGAGGUGGAGGCUGGGGGCCAGGCCAAGAACAGGAGGGGAGUCGGAGCAGAGCCAAGCUGGACUCCCUGUGUCUUUGGGACUCUGCCUUGAUACUGCCAUCGGUAACCCACCUGCAUUCUGUUCUAUAUGUGAGGUCUGGAGGUUGCACCUUAAAACGUGGUAGAAAUCAGUCAGCAUAUGCAUACUGUGCAUACUGAAUGCCUGUCGUGUGCUCAGCCGGCUUCCUGCCCUCCGCACAGCGGAGGACCACUGGCUGACUUAGAGUUCUGGCCACAGGUGUCCAAGUCGCUAUCCAUGCGGUCACCUUCCAACCAGCCUUAGACCUCGAGAGCAGGGCUGGGCAGAGCUGGGCAGGGCCUGACCUGCCCACCUGGGGGCAAACACUACACAGGCUCCCUUUAUCAGAAGGACGAUAGUAUGAAUAGUGAUUGUUCCUACCAUCAUCACUCAACCUCGCUGGUCCCCUGGUGGCUCUUCUCAGAUCAGAGGCUGCCAGGAAGGAAUUUUGAGGCUCCAGGACUAGCCCAAACUCACACUGUGGGGAGUGUGCACUGAGUGCUAUGCUCCUGGCUUAGGGAAGAGCAGUUCUGCCUAGGAUCUUUCUAGAAUCAGAGGGUCACAGAUCCAAGUUGGAAAGGCCCUUAAAGGGCUCCACCUGACCUUUCAUCAUGGAGAUGAGCAAGCUGAGGCCCAGGGAGGGCUUGGUGUGAAGGCAUCAGUAGCCCUGGGCUCCUGGCAGGAAGCUGGUGGCUUGGAGGGGACUGGAGCCUUGGGGUGUGGACAGGGAGCUAGCUCACCAGCUCCAGGGUUCCCUUUUGGAGCCUCGAGUCAUGGGACCAGGUGUGCUGAAGGUGAUGGCCCUGUGCCUGGUGGCACAUCACCUGUCACCCGGAUGCUGCCUGGGGUAGGAGCUGGGUGAUCAUAGCACAUGGAGGCCUGACUGGCUCAGGGAGGGUAGGAGGUGCUCCUCCCCGGAGCCCACAGGCACCUGCUGGGUGCUUGCUGGCUCCAGAUAUGGAUGGCAUCUGAGCAUCAAGUGAUCAAGACCUUCAUUUUGGCGGGGGUGGGGAUGGGAGGCGACAGUAACCAAAUUCACAAGAUAGUAACUCUUCCCCAAAGCAUCUGUGGCUCUUGAGGCUAACUUGGCCAGUACAGCGGCCUGUGUUACCCGAAAUGCAACUCCACCCUCUGUCAUUGUUCCUGAACCGGGGAGGGCAGAGCUGCAGGAGAGUGGGAGGCAUAUGGCUGAGGGCAGGUUUGGGUGCAGAACUGUGGAGGGGCAGGGCCGGCCUCCCAGUGAAUAAGCCCC